ACAGCUCCCCCGCAGCCAGAAGCCGGGCCUGCAGCGCCUCAGCACCGCUCCGGGACACCCCACCCGCUUCCCAGGCGUGACCUGUCAACAGCAACUUCGCGGUGUGGUGAACUCUCUGAGGAAAAACGUAAGUUCGAGCCCUGAUUCCUCCGCUUCCCCGCAGGGUGACCUUGGGCUUGUGCCCCCAGCACCACCCCUGUCCCGGGUCCCUGUUUUCUCUCUGGAAAUGGGUUGAAGACCAAAGAAAAUAAUGUGCGCCACUUGGGUCACCCCGGGCCGCCUGCCCCGGAAAAUUGGCCCCAGUUGAGGAGUUGUGGCUGUAAGGAUGCCUUGAACCGAGGCGGCGGUGCUCGUGGUUGGAGCUCUCCAGGGUGGGUGCGCAUUUGUAAUGCGGUGGAUGCUCUGGGACUCGGCCCCUCUGAAGGUGCUGGGGGUUGGGGACGGCCCAGGCAGUGGCGUAGGCGUCCUAGGAAGGCGGGAGCAGAGGCAGAAAUGUCGCUGCAAGACCGUAGUCAGGGUCCUUGACCACAGGGGUCACUUGUGACCAACCACAUGGUCUGUUGUUCCUCCUGCCCCCUGGUUCAGCCCAGGAAACACUGGUGCUCAGGUUUGGAGCCAGAGAUUUGCACUGAAAGGGCGGGAUUGAGUCGCCAGUUGUCAGUUUCCUCAGCAGUAUUUGCGGAGGUUUUCACAGGAGGCCGUUGCUUCGUAAAUAUUAUACAUGUAUUCUUCUUUUUGGAGCAUUUUGAUUAUUACUCUCAGACGUGCGUGGCAACAAGUGACUGAGACCUAGAAAUCCAAGCGUUGGAGGUCCUGAGGCCAGCCUAAGUCGCUUCAAAAUGGAACGAAGGCGUUUGUGGGGUUCCAUUCAGAGCCGAUACAUCAGCAUGAGUGUGUGGACAAGCCCACGGAGACUUGUGGAGCUGGCAGGGCAGAGCCUGCUGAAGGAUGAGGCCCUGGCCAUUGCCGCCCUGGAGUUGCUGCCCAGGGAGCUCUUCCCGCCACUCUUCAUGGCAGCCUUUGACGGGAGACACAGCCAGACCCUGAAGGCAAUGGUGCAGGCCUGGCCCUUCACCUGCCUCCCUCUGGGAGUGCUGAUGAAGGGACAACAUCUUCACCUGGAGACCUUCAAAGCUGUGCUUGAUGGACUUGAUGUGCUCCUUGCCCAGGAGGUUCGCCCCAGGAGGUGGAAACUUCAAGUGCUGGAUUUACGGAAGAACUCUCAUCAGGACUUCUGGACUGUAUGGUCUGGAAACAGGGCCAGUCUGUACUCAUUUCCAGAGCCAGAAGCAGCUCAGCCCAUGACAAAGAAGCGAAAAGUAGAUGGUUUGAGCACAGAGGCAGAGCAGCCCUUCAUUCCAGUAGAGGUGCUCGUAGACCUGUUCCUCAAGGAAGGUGCCUGUGAUGAAUUGUUCUCCUACCUCAUUGAGAAAGUGAAGCGAAAGAAAAAUGUACUACGCCUGUGCUGUAAGAAGCUGAAGAUUUUUGCAAUGCCCAUGCAGGAUAUCAAGAUGAUCCUGAAAAUGGUGCAGCUGGACUCUAUUGAAGAUUUGGAAGUGACUUGUACCUGGAAGCUACCCACCUUGGCGAAAUUUUCUCCUUACCUGGGCCAGAUGAUUAAUCUGCGUAGACUCCUCCUCUCCCACAUCCAUGCAUCUUCCUACAUUUCCCCGGAGAAGGAAGAGCAGUAUAUCGCCCAGUUCACCUCUCAGUUCCUCAGUCUGCAGUGCCUGCAGGCUCUCUAUGUGGACUCUUUAUUUUUCCUUAGAGGCCGCCUGGAUCAGUUGCUCAGGCACGUGAUGAACCCCUUGGAAACCCUCUCAAUAACUAACUGCCGGCUUUCGGAAGGGGAUGUGAUGCAUCUGUCCCAGAGUCCCAGCGUCAGUCAGCUAAGUGUCCUGAGUCUAAGUGGGGUCAUGCUGACCGAUGUAAGUCCCGAGCCCCUCCAAGCUCUGCUGGAGAGAGCCUCUGCCACCCUCCAGGACCUGGUCUUUGAUGAGUGUGGGAUCACGGAUGAUCAGCUCCUUGCCCUCCUGCCUUCCCUGAGCCACUGCUCCCAGCUUACGACCUUAAGCUUCUACGGGAAUUCCAUCUCCAUAUCUGCCCUGCAGAGUCUCCUGCAGCACCUCAUCGGGCUGAGCAAUCUGACCCACGUGCUGUAUCCUGUCCCCCUGGAGAGUUAUGAGGACAUCCAUGGUACCCUCCACCUGGAGAGGCUUGCCUAUCUGCAUGCCAGGCUCAGGGAGUUGCUGUGUGAGUUGGGGCGGCCCAGCAUGGUCUGGCUUAGUGCCAACCCCUGUCCUCACUGUGGGGACAGAACCUUCUAUGACCCGGAGCCCAUCCUGUGCCCCUGUUUCAUGCCUAAUUAGCUGGGUGCACAUAUCAAAUGCUUCAUUCUGCAUACUUGGACACUAAAGCCAGGAUGUGCAUGCAUCUUGAAGCAACAAAGCAGCCACAGUUUCAGACAAAUGUUCAGUGUGAGUGAGGAAAACAUGUUCAGUGAGGAAAAAACAUUCAGACAAAUGUUCAGUGAGGAAAAAAAGGGGAAGUUGGGGGUAGGCAGAUGUUGACUUGAGGAGUUAAUGUGAUCUUUGGGGAGAUACAUCUUAUAGAGUUAGAAAUAGAAUCUGAAUUUCUAAAGGGAGAUUCUGGCUUGGGAAGUACAUGUAGGAGUUAAUCCCUGUGUAGACUGUUGUAAAGAAACUGUUGAAAAUAAAGAGAAGCAAUGUGAAGCA